ACGAGUCGGCGGCGCUACCGAGGGGCUGUGGGCGCGCAGCUGGAACCUCCGGCUGUCAGUGCGCUUACAGUUCCUAACCCCGACCCUGCGCGCAGCCCGCACUAUGGCAGCCCCGCCGCAGCUAAGGGCUCUGCUCGUAGUCGUCAACGCACUGCUGCGCAAGCGCCGCUACCACGCUGCGUUGGCCGUGCUUAAGGGCUUCCGGAACGGGGCUGUCUAUGGAGCCAAAAUCCGGGCCCCUCACGCGCUGGUCAUGACCUUUCUCUUCCGGAAUGGCAGCCUCCAGGAGAAGCUGUGGGCCAUACUGCAGGCCACAUAUAUCCACUCCUGGAACCUGGCACGGUUUGUGUUCACCUACAAGGGUCUCCGUGCCCUGCAGUCCUACAUACAAGGCAAGACCUACCCAGCACACGCAUUCCUGGCGGCCUUCCUCGGGGGUAUCCUGGUGUUUGGAGAAAACAAUAACAUCAACAGCCAGAUCAACAUGUACCUGUUGUCACGCGUCCUGUUUGCCCUGAGCCGCCUGGCUGUAGAGAAGGGCUACAUCCCUGAACCCAGGUGGGACCCGUUCCCGCUGCUCACUGCGGUGGUGUGGGGGCUGGUGCUGUGGCUCUUUGAGUAUCACCGAUCCACCCUGCAGCCCUCGCUGCAGUCCUCCAUGACCUACCUCUAUGAGGACAGCAAUGUAUGGCACGACAUCUCAGACUUCCUCGUCUAUAACAAGAGCCGUCCCUCCAAUUAAUGCAGCCCUGAGGUGUCUGGCUGUGGCUCAAGAUUUGGCCCCAUGCAGACCCUCCCAAAGGAUACUGCCUUCUCAAGAUCAUAGGCCUCAGACUCCAACUGGUGUUAUCCCAGGGUUCCGUUUGCUGAAGUAAAAACACUGAUUUUAAAAUCCCAGUGGGUACCUUUGUAUGGUGGCACAAGUGGCCGAAUCAGGCUGAGGAAUCUACGGCUUGGUUCCAGCUGUGCAGCUGACUUCUGUGAGACUGGGGCCAGCCACACUACUCUCUAGGCCUCAGGGGUCAAGGAGCUCAGAGGAGGGCCCUGAGGUCUCUUUCCGGUGGGUAUGUUCAUUCUUCAACUGUUCUUAUGUCACAGAGGGCUCCUUGCUGGUGGGCAGUGGGUUGUAAAUACUUUUUAAAAAACACUAAGUUCCUUAUCUCAGAUGCUGUUCUACUGGAGAAGUUCUAGAUUCCCACUGUCCAAUAGAAACACGUGAGCCAUAUAUGUAAUUAAAAUGUUUCUAGUAGCUGCAUUACAAAAAAGAAGCCUGGGCACUGUGGCUCACUCCUGUAAUCUCAGAACUUUGGGAGGCUGAGGCAGGUGGAUCACUUGAGCUCAGGAGCUUGAGACCAGCCUGGGCAACAUGGUGAAACCCAGUUUCUACAAAAAAUACAAAAAAUUAGCCGGGUUCCAUCACCUGUGGUUCCAGCUGAGGUGGGAGGAUCACUUGAGCCUAUGAGGUCGAGGCUACAGUGAGCAAAGAUCACGCCACUGCACUCCAGCCUGGGCGACAGUGAGACCCUGUCUCACCAAAGAAAAAAAAAAGGUGAGAUUAAUCUUCACUAUAUAUUUUAACACAAAUUUCUAAAAGUUAUUUCAACAUAUAAUUAACAUCAUUAGAUAUUUUGUACUCUUUUUUGUAUUAAGUAUUCAAAAUUGGGUGUAUAUUUUGCCACCCACAUUUUCAGGACCCAGUAGCCACAUGUGGCUAGUGGCUGCUGUGACGGGCAACACAGAUAUGGAACACUUGUAUCCUCACAGAUUAUUCUAGUGGACAGUGCAGAUCUAGAGCUAGAGGACAUGGGUUUGAGUCCCCACUCCCCCACUGUGUAACCUUGGGGAAGGUUCUGGACCUCUCAGAGCCUCAAUUUAUCAUAAAAUGAGGAUAAUCAUAAUGCCGUGGUCCUCACUGGACUUGUGCAACUACCACUGAUGUGCUACUAAUUACUUUCAUUUAGUGCAUUCAUACUUCCACUUGGGUGUUUUCCACAUAUUAUUAUUAUUUUUUUUUUUUAAGUAGCGACAGGGUCUCGCUCUGUCACUAGGGCUAGUCUCGACCUCCUAGCCUCAAGCAAUCUUCCUGCCUCAGUCUCCCAAAGUGCCAUGAUUACAGGCAUGAGCCACUGCCCCUAGCCUGCACAUAUUAUUUUUAAACCAUACAGUGGCCUUGCAAAUGUGUGUUUUCGUCCCCAUUUUACAGAUGUAGAAACUGAGGGUCAGGCCAGGUGCAGUGGCUCACGCCUGUAAUCCCAGCACUUUGGGAGGCUGAGGCAGGCAGAUAACCUGAGAUCAGGAGUUCUUGACCAGCCUGGCCAACAUGGUAAAACCCCAUCUCUACUAAAAAUACAAAAAUUAGCCAGGCAUGGUGGCACGUCCCUGUAAUCCCAGCUACUGGGGAGGCUGAGGCAGGAGAAUCGCUUGAACCUGGGAGGCAGAGGCUGCAGUGAGCUGAGAUCGCACGACUGCACUCCAGCCUGGGCCACAGAGCGAGACUGUGUCUAAAAAAAAAAUAAAAAAAGAAAAGAAAAGAAACUGAGAAUCAGAGAGGAGAGUAACUUGCCCAAGGUAAUACAGCUAGUAUAACAGCCGAAUCAAGAUUUGAACUCAGAUUCGUCUGAUUUCAAAGCCCAUGUUUUUUCCAGUGCCUUGUUUCAAAUUUAGAAACCUAAGCCAUGCUAUGCAAAUGUUAGCUCAUUAUAGGAUAUGGGCCAGAAAGGGGUACACAUUCAAAUGCCCAUAGGGGCCUACAAUGACAUAGUGCUAUGCGAUGAGGAGUGAUGGGGACAUAGGGAACUGGAGACUUGUGUACCAGUCUGAUUUUUUCUUUUUUUUUUUUUUUUGAGACAGAGUCUUGCUCUCUCGCCCAGGCUGGAGUGCAGUGGCGCGAUCUUGGCUCACUGCAAGCUCUGCCUCCCAGGUUUACUUACACCAUUCUCCUGCCUCAGCCUCCGGAGUAGCUGGGCCUACAGGUGCCCGCCACCACACCCGGCUAAUUUUUUGUAUUUUUAGUAGAGAUGGGGUUUCACCGUGUUAGCCAGGAUGGUCUCAAUCUCCUGACCUCAUGAUCCACCCACCUUGGCCUCCCAAAAUGCUGGGAUUACAGGUGUGAGCCACCAUGCCUGGCCAAGUCUGCUUUUUUCGAAACCACGAUCCUAGACCAGGCACGGUGGCUUGCACCUGUAAUCCCAGCACUUUGGGAGGCCGAGGCGGGUGGAUCACCUGAGGUCAGGAGUUCGAGACCAGCCUGGCCAACAUGGCGAAAUCCUGUCUCUACUAAAAAUACAAAAAUUAGCUGGACAUGGUGGCAGGCACCUGUAAUUCCAGCUACUUGGGAGGCUGAGGUGGGAGAAUCUCUUGAACCUGGGGGGCUGCUGUGAGCCGAGAUAGUUCCAUUACACUUCAGCCUGGGUGACAGAGUAAGACUCUGUCUCAAAAAAAAAAAAAAAAAAAAAAACACAAUCCUGGACAAAUCAAACAAGUCUCCAGGAAAAUCUGGUCCAUGGGCUACCAAUUUGAGACCAUUGGUCUGGUAGAUACACUUUCAUUAAUAUACUUACUCCAUCACUCUUUCUAUAUUUUAGAAGUUACUAGUAGAAAUGUAUGCAGGAGUCACUGGAGACCUUAUUAAAAUGCAGCUUCUGAUUCAGUGAGCUGGGGUGGGGCCUGAGAGUCUGCAUUUCUCCCAGGCUCCCUGGUGCUGCCAGUGGUGCUGCUCUGAGUAACAAGGGGGUGGGGAAUGAUAUGGAGCCGUCCAUUAUUAUCCCAUCUGACAAAUGAGUCACAGAGCCCUUAGGUAAUUGAGGUGGGAUCAGUCUGAUUCUGUAAGCUGUGUUUUCAGCCACAACAUUUACUGCAAACUUGGAGUAGGUAAUUAUGAAGUUCCUUUAACUUGCUGUGGAGGUUGAAUGAGCUCUAGAGUAAGGGGUCCGCAACCCCGGUACCGGUCCAUGGCCUGUUCGGAACCAGGCCACGCAGCAGGAGUUGAAAGGUGGGUGAGCUAGCGAAGCUUCAUCUGUAUGUACAGCCACUCCCCACUGCUCACAUUACCACCUGAGCUCUGCCUUCUGUCAGAUCAGUGGUGGCAUUAGAUGCUCGUAGGAAUGCAAACCCUAUUGUGAACUGCGCAUGCAAGGGAUCUAGGUUGCAUGCUCCUUAUGAGAAUCUAAUGCCUGAUGAUCUGUCACUGUCUCCCGUCACGCCUUGAUGGGACUGUCUAGUUGCUGGAAAACAAACUCAGGGCUCCCACUGAUUCUACAUUAUGGUGUGUUGUACAAUUAUUUCAUUAUAUAUUACAAGGUAAUAAUAAUAGAAAUAAAAUCCACAGUAAAUGCAAUGUGCUUGAAUCAUCCUGAAACCACGUCCCCUCCCCAGUGGUCCGUGGAAAAAUUAUCUUCCCCAAAACUGGUCCCUGGUGCCAAAAAGGUUGGGGACUGCUGCUCUAGGGGUUGGGGAGGGCAGAGGGCUUGGGCCAUCACCAGGCAGGUUUUAUAGCAGAUGGUGGGGGUGCCCUGCCUAUAGCUCCUCUAAAUAACGACUCUGGUGCACACUAGCCAGCUUUGCCAGUGGCCGCCCCUCUGUCUUUCUGCCUGAGGACUCUAGCUUGUCACUGGUGCCUCCUUUGCCAGCCUCUGGCAGGCCUGAAGGGCUGGAGAAUGAACACAUCCUUGGAGCAACCUUCAACCAAUGACUGAUAAAUACCCCCACUCCCACAGCCCGCAUCCCUCACCCCUCGGGUGGGAUAACUCAGAGGUGCGUGCUCCACACUGACUCCCAGGGCCGCCCAGCAGGGCUGAGCCUCAAACACCCUCCCCAUCUCCCUUCCUCAUGCCCCUACCAGUGCUUCCUGGGACCACUUCCCAUAUGAACCACUUGCACUCAAACCCUUGUCUUAGAGUCUGCUAUUGGGGGAACCCAAACUAAAACUGGCCUCUGUACAGCAGGUUGAGAGGCAAUAUAGCAUGGUGGUCAGGGACAUAGGCUUUGGAGCCAGAGUGCCUGGGCUCAAGCCCUGGCCCCACAGUUUCCUUGGGCAAGUGACUGAGCCAUUCUGUGCCUCUAUUUCCUCAUUGAUAAAGUAGGCGUUGUCGUAGCACACACCUCAUCGAGUGGUGUGGAGGGUUAAAGAAUAUGACACAGUUAAAGUGAGUCCCCAAUAAAUGCUGUUAUUUCUAAGAGCAUCCAAAUGUAGAGGAAGUGUGCCCCUGAGGACUGAGCACACCCUGCUUUUAGCCUGUCCUGCCCCCAGCUGAAGGUGAAACCUUGGCCGCCUGCCCUCCUGAAGUCCCGCCACUGCUGCUGGGGGUUGGCCAACUCCGCUACCGACUGUCUCUGCUCUCUAAGAAUAGGUUUCCCUCACAGAUGGCAUCUCUCUGGAUGCUGCUAGAGCAUCUGGUGCUUCCAACUGCACACUCCAGGGAGGAAGGCAGUGUGGUCUGUGCCGGGGAGCAGGGCUCUGCCUUCCAGCAGAUCUGAGAGGAGUCCCAUUUGGCUCCUUCCUAGCUGCCCUCCAUUCUCUAAGACCUGUAAAACAGGGAUGGCCAGAGGGCUCUUGUUGCACAGUAAGUGCUAUGCUUCCUAAAUGCUAGUUCCUGAAAUAGAAUGGUUUAACCUCUACUUACUAAACACCUGCUACAAUCCUGUUAAUUCUUUUGACAUGUAAGACUAAAAUAAAUAAAUAAAUAAAUAAA